GGGUGGGCGGAGCGGGCCCCCCGAGCGGGGGCUGGCGAGCGCGGGGAGGGGGCCGAAAGGGCGGCAAAGCCGGCGCGCGCCCGGCUGGGGGCGGAGGGCGGGGGCCCGCGGGCCGGAACAGCCGCGGCAAGUGGCGGCGGCGGCAGCGGCAGCGGAGGCAGCUGAGGCGGCGGCGGCGAGUGGGGGUCCGGGCGGCGGCGGCGGGCCCGGCGGCGGGCCGAGGAGCCGGGCGCAAUGGAGCGGAAGAGGUGGGAGUGCCCGGCGCUCCCGCAGGGCUGGGAGAGGGAAGAAGUGCCCAGAAGGUCGGGGCUGUCGGCCGGCCACAGGGAUGUCUUUUACUAUAGCCCGAGCGGGAAGAAGUUCCGCAGCAAGCCGCAGCUGGCGCGCUACCUGGGCGGCUCCAUGGACCUGAGCACCUUCGACUUCCGCACGGGCAAGAUGCUGAUGAGCAAGAUGAACAAGAGCCGCCAGCGCGUGCGCUACGACUCCUCCAACCAGGUCAAGGGCAAGCCCGACCUGAACACGGCGCUGCCCGUGCGCCAGACGGCGUCCAUCUUCAAGCAGCCGGUGACCAAGAUUACCAACCACCCCAGCAACAAGGUCAAGAGCGACCCGCAGAAGGCGGUGGACCAGCCGCGCCAGCUCUUCUGGGAGAAGAAGCUGAGCGGCCUGAACGCCUUCGACAUUGCUGAGGAGCUGGUCAAGACCAUGGACCUCCCCAAGGGCCUGCAGGGGGUGGGACCUGGCUGCACGGAUGAGACGCUGCUGUCGGCCAUCGCCAGCGCCCUGCACACUAGCACCAUGCCCAUCACGGGACAGCUCUCGGCCGCCGUGGAGAAGAACCCCGGCGUAUGGCUCAACACCACGCAGCCCCUGUGCAAAGCCUUCAUGGUGACCGACGAGGACAUCAGGAAGCAGGAAGAGCUGGUGCAGCAGGUGCGGAAGCGGCUGGAGGAGGCGCUGAUGGCCGACAUGCUGGCGCACGUGGAGGAGCUGGCCCGUGACGGGGAGGCGCCGCUGGACAAGGCCUGCGCUGAGGACGACGACGAGGAAGACGAGGAGGAGGAGGAGGAGGAGCCCGACCCGGACCCGGAGAUGGAGCACGUCUAGGGCAGAGGCCCUGCCGAGAGCCCGUGCUGCCUGCUGGAGCCGCCUGCAGACGCGGUCCUCGGCCCCACGUGAACCAGGCUCGGCGGCGAAGCCCAGCCUUGGAGACACCCAGGAGGAAGGCCGUGCUCCUGGCUCCCUCCUCGGCCCGUCCCCACUUCCCGGGGCCUCGGGGCACACAGCUGGGGCUGCCCCCACCCGAAAGACCCUCCACGCUCGUCCUCUACAGAGUCCGGCUUCGGGAAGUGCCGGGUGCUCCUGGGCCCUGCCUGGCUCCCUACGACCUUUGGGCUCGAGGCCAGCUCCUCCCCAUGCCCGCUGUCCCAGCUCCUUGAGACUGGAGAGCAGCCAGCAGGUGCCCGGCAGCUCGGCGCCACGGCUUGCUGACAGCUGGGAGGGUUUCUCGGUCUGGAGGCGUAGUUUUGAAACUCACAUCACCCACUGUGCAGCGUGAGGACGGGACUCUGGUCUGCUGUGGGGGGCAUGCAGGACGGCGCCACUCUCUGCCCUGCCAUGCGGCUGGUGGUGCCACAGAGCCUCACCGUGCCUGAGUGGCAUGCCCAGGAGGCCGCUCUCCUUCAGUAAAUGUAACACAGUCGAGGCACGUCAUCGGGCAGCCUUCCCUGUGUGCCAACGCCAGCCUUCGCUUCUGAAAACCAAACUCCAGCCGCUGCCAGUCGGGACUUGGUCGCCCGGCGCUGCCAGAAUGCUCCACUGCCAGCCGGCCCCCCUGCCUCGGUUUCCCUUCUGUUUAGUGGCGACACAGGCACCCAGCUUUGGGGUGGUGCUGACGCUCCCAGGGGUGCCAGGAGCCACUGGGACAGGGUGAGGCUCCCAGACGCUCCUCGAGGUGCCCAGCUCUCCAGGGAGCUUCUGGCCCAAGGCCGUCUGAGGGAUCUGCUCCUUAACCCCCCAGUGCCUUGGCGAGGGCAGGUUCCAAGCCACAGACGCCUGCCCCGAGUGGACUCUGCGGCCAGUCCCUGGUGCCCUCCUGGCCCUGCUGCCCAGUGAGGGCUCCUACGGGUGGGUUCAUUGGCCUGGGCCCAGCGAGCCCCCACCUGCAUUGACCUUAGGCCCAUAGAGAGGGCCUGUCCCGGUGCUGCCCCAGCCAGGAUCUGGUCGCUGCCCCAGGGGGACUGAUGGGCAGAGUCGCCCCUGUGGCUGGACUGUGACCAUCCCUGAUGGGGCCUGACCGCGGGAGCUGAGGAAGCGCCGCUCCACCGUCUGCCCUCCAAGGACCCGCAUGGAGGCAGUGGGCUGGCAGCUUCCUGCUGCUCCCUGUCAGAGUCAAAGCACAAAUCCUCAGGACGGGCUCAAGGGCCAGGGCAGCCGAGGGAAGCUCCAGGUGGGGACCACGUCUUCCUGAGGUUGGUGCCCACUGGCUGGGACCCUUUGCAGUGGGGUGGCCUCCCCUCUGUCUGCCUGGUGGAGGGAGCCGUGGGCGUGGGGACGUGACUGAAUAAAGCCACCAUGGGUGGAUGUGCUUGGAGCCUGGAGUUCGGUGCGUCCGCUAGACUUUGGUGCCCACGUUUGAGCUUCUGUCUUUGGUUGGGUGAUGAAAGGCUGAAAGCGGUGUGGGGACAGGGCCAGCAGGUCCCCCAACCUCGCGGACAUUCACAACCCAAGAGUCAGGCUUAGGGGUAUUCAGAGAAGACCAGGCCGGCCUGGGCAUCUGUGGGCAAGGGCCGUGCCCCCUGAGGUGCCGCUGGCUCAGCCUAGGGAUCGUGGGUCUUGGCCCUGCUGCCCCGGUGAGGAAGAUGGGCUGGGGCUCAGACCCAGCACCGCUCCUUCCAAAGGAAGGGAAGCAGGAGGGGCUGCCUGGCAGGGAGGGCCCCCCAGGUCCUCAGGUCCUGCACAGCCGCUGCAGGGAGGGGAGCUGUGCCCCGGGACCCUGGACUUCAGCUCACUAGCCAUGGCCACUGGAAGCUGCUUUCUGGACCUGAAGGCUGGGAGGCCACCCUCCCCUCAUCUGCCCGGCACUCAGAGACACUCUGUUUCCCUCUUCCCAUCUCCCACUGUGUCCCUGUCUCCCUUGGUCUCUCUCUGUCUCUGUCUAUCCCUGUCUCUAUCUCUCCCUCUUGUCUCUCUCUUGCGCCGUCUCCCUCUCUGUCCCUCUUUGUUUCUUGCUCUCUCUCCUGUCUCUCUCCCUCGGUCUCUGUCUCUGUCUCUUGCUGUCUCUCCCUCUCUGUCGCAGCCCAGCUUCCUGUCACUGACAGACCCCGAUCAGUCCCUCUGAUCCCGGGGUUCUGGCCAUGUCCUGGCCUUGGUCUGAGAUGUGAUGAUCCCUACCCCUGCCACAGGGCCCUCCCCACUGGAAGCCCAUCCAGGCCCUGGGCUGUCGCUGUUGACGAAGCUUGAGGGUCCUUUCCUCUCUCCCUGAAACCUUGGGGACCCCCACAGGCCAAGGCAAUACUGGCCUUUGCUAGAGGUCGUGCCCGGUGAGAAGUGAGUUGUAGGCGUGGGCACCUGAGGGGCCAGCCCAGUGCUCAGGCCCUCGUCAAAUUCCCUGCCCUGGAAAAGUCUCAGACCCUCAGGCUGAACCCCCUGGGCGCACCGAGGCUCCACACUCCAGCCCCAGAACCCAGACCUGGCAUGGGGCGGGGAAGCCUGAGCUCCCAAUGCUGGGAUCUUUCGUGGGGGCCUCAUGACCAGCCUGCCCUGUGCGGUGCCUGGCCCCAUCCUCAAAGGCCACUUGGCUGCCCCCAGCCCCGCCCAUGUCUCAGCCCCAAGACCUUCUGGGACUUUUUUUUUUUUUAGACAAGAGUUUCGCUCUUCUUUCGCUCUUGUUGCACAGGCUGGAGUGCAGUGGCGUGAUCUGGGCUCACUGCAACCUCCACCUUCUGGGUUCAAGCCUCAGCCUCCCGAGUAGCCACCACGCCCAGCUAAUUUUUGUAUUUUUAAUAGAGACAGGGUUUCACCAUGUUGGCCAGUCUGGUCUGGAACUCCUAACCUCAGGUGAUCCGCCCGCCCCAGCUUCCCAAAUUGCCGGGAUUACAGGUGUGAACCACCAUGGCAGCCCUUCUGGCACUUGCCAGCAGCAGCAAGAGCCUCACGUGUCCCCCGCCUCCCCUCAGACCAAGCUCCCCACCGCUGCCGCCACAGAGGGUACCAGGGAGGAGAGGCUCAGGACCCCCGUGGCGAGGAUGCACCUCCCAGCCCUCGGCCCAGCCACACGGACCACAGGGCUCCCGAGUCUCAGCAACACCAGCUAAGGGGCAUCAUGCCUCUCCUGCCACACCCAGGGCCCGUGCCUUGCUGUCCCUGCAGCCCCCAGACCCAGGCAGACAGGGACAGCCCUUCUGACCACCGCACACACUCGCCACCGCAAAGAUCCCCGGGGAUGCCCCUCGCCUGUGUGUGUCCCUCAUGGCUGUCACAGCAAAUCUCCAGGAGCCCGGAGGUGCCCAUGGAAAACACCCCCAGCUUCCGGAACGUUCUUUCGGACAGGGCCAUACCGGAGCAAGACUCAGCUUUCUGGUAGCGGGUGGCUGGGCACUGCCUGUGAGAUUCUGUCACACUCGCUCCAGAUUCAAGGGGUCCAAAAAGUGUAAACAAGUCAAGUGCCCAUCCAGGGAUGAACGAACACAGCCCGGCCCGGCCACACCAUGGAGCAGGACUCGGCCAUGAACAGGAACCAGGCUCUGACACCGGCCACGGCGCAGAUGCCCCUGGAGGAGUCCACCCUCAGCAAGAGACACACAGACACCGACACGGCGUGCAAUCCCAUUUGUGUGAAUGUCCAGGACAGGCCGAUUCAGAGACAGGAAGGGGACACGUGGGUGCCAGUGACUGGGGAUUAUGGGGACUGGGGGAAAUGGCUAAAGGGCACCCACAAAAGUUAAUGAUAAUGUUCCACAGUUUUUUUUUUGAGAUGGAGUCUCACUCUUGUCACCCAGGCUGGAGUGCAAUGGUGUGAUCUCUGCUCACUGCAAGCUCUGCCUCCUGGGUUCACGCCAUUCUCCCUCCUCAGCCUCCCAAGUAGCUGAGAUUACAGGCAUAUGCCACCACCCCCAGUAGAGACGGGGUUUCACCAUGUUAGCCAGGCUGGUCACGAACUCCUGACCUCAAGUGAUCCCCCACCUCGGCCUCCCAAAGUGCUGGGAUUACAGGCAUGAGCCACCGUGCCUCACCAGAAUUGUGUACUUUUUUUUCUUCUUCUUCUUCGGCAUGGAGUUUCGCUCUUGUUGCCCAGGCUGGAGUGCAAUGGUGCAAACUUGGCUCACCGCAACCUCCUCCUCCCGGGUUCAAUAGAUUCUCCAGCCUCAGCCUGCUGAGUAGCUGAGAUUACGGGCGCCCGCCACCACACCCAGCUAAUCUUUGUACUUUUAGUAGAGACAGGGUUUCACCAUGUUGGCCACGGGCAAAAGAAUUUUGUUGAGGGCAAAUAAUAUGAGACCACAAAACUGCCUUCCCUGCUCAGUUUUAAUUUUCACAGUUUUAAUUUUUAGCCUUCUCUGGUUACCAAAAUAACCACGCUCACGGCCGUUCAUUUGAAGAUAUUUCCAGUUAACGUGUGUGAAGUGGGUUUUUUGAGAUGUAAUUUACAAGCAAUAAAAUGCUCCUGUCUCUGC